UUUGCCUAAUUGCCCUGGGAGGCUGGCAGGGACGUUCCCUGCAGCCGUGGAUCCGCUGACUGCAGAGACCCUACCUGGCACUCUAAGUUGGUGCGUCAGCAUUUUAGGUUGAAAUGAAUGAAAAAUCAAUCAGGAUGACUGCAGUGGUAGCGUGCACAACUCUAACCUAGUUUGUUCAUAAUUUUCAACUAUUCACCGUAGACCCAAGCAGUAUGUAAGAUGUGAAGAAGAUUCUUUGGGCUAUAAAGAUGAAGAGUCUACUUCUUCUGGUGCUGAUUUCAAUCUGCUGGGCUGAUCAUCUUUCAGACAACUAUACUCUGGAUCAUGACAGAGCUAUUCACAUCCAAGAAAAUGGCCCCCAUCUACUUGUGGAAGCAGAGCAAGCCAAGGUGUUUUCACACAGAGGUGGCAAUGUUACACUGCCAUGUAAAUUUUAUCGAGACCCUACAGCAUUUGGCUCAGGAAUCCAUAAAAUCCGAAUUAAGUGGACCAAGCUAACUUCGGAUUACCUCAAGGAAGUGGAUGUUUUUGUUUCCAUGGGAUACCACAAAAAAACCUAUGGAGGCUACCAGGGUAGAGUGUUUCUGAAGGGAGGCAGUGAUAGUGAUGCUUCUCUGGUCAUCACAGACCUCACUCUGGAAGAUUAUGGGAGAUAUAAGUGUGAGGUGAUUGAAGGAUUAGAAGAUGAUACUGUUGUGGUAGCACUGGACUUACAAGGUGUGGUAUUCCCUUACUUUCCACGACUGGGGCGCUACAAUCUCAAUUUUCACGAGGCGCAGCAGGCGUGUCUGGACCAGGAUGCUGUGAUCGCCUCCUUCGACCAGCUGUACGACGCCUGGCGGGGCGGGCUGGACUGGUGCAAUGCCGGCUGGCUCAGUGAUGGCUCUGUGCAAUAUCCCAUCACAAAGCCCAGAGAGCCCUGUGGGGGGCAGAACACAGUGCCCGGAGUCAGGAACUACGGAUUUUGGGAUAAAGAUAAAAGCAGAUAUGAUGUUUUCUGUUUUACAUCCAAUUUCAAUGGCCGUUUUUACUAUCUGAUCCACCCCACCAAACUGACCUAUGAUGAAGCGGUGCAAGCUUGUCUCAAUGAUGGUGCUCAGAUUGCAAAAGUGGGCCAGAUAUUUGCUGCCUGGAAAAUUCUCGGAUAUGACCGCUGUGAUGCGGGCUGGUUGGCGGAUGGCAGCGUCCGCUACCCCAUCUCUAGGCCAAGAAGGCGCUGCAGUCCUACUGAGGCUGCAGUGCGCUUCGUGGGUUUCCCAGAUAAAAAGCAUAAGCUGUAUGGUGUCUACUGCUUCAGAGCAUACAACUGAAUGUGCCCUUAGAGCGCAUCAGUUUUAAAGUCAUUAAGAACAUGUGAAAGGUGUUUUUUUUUUCCAAUAUGAACUCAUGCAAGUUACCAAAACUGUGAUAACCCUUUUUUACUUACUGUAAAGAGUCAUUUUCAUAAAGAUCAAUUCAUUGAUUUGUUUUUUGUAAAGCUAUCAUUCAAUAUAUAUUAUAAAUUAAUAUAAAUUUAAGGGAAGCUCUAUGUAAGGAGACUUAGAGCCAAACUGUUUAAGCUGUAUCAUCCCAACAAAGUAUCCUUUCAUGAACGGGGCAUGCAAUAGCUUAAGAAUUGCUAGGAUUAAAUUAAGGAAAGUAAAGCUACUCAGAGCAGCAGGUUCCACAAGCACAAACUUUACACAUUUGUACAAUUUUGAAAUGCACUACAAUAAACAAAUUAGAGCAACACAUUUGAAAUACAGGCUUCUUUACAUAAACUGAGAGGUUAUACAAAACUCAGUUUCACAAGGGAACAAUCUAUACCUUUCUAAAAGUUAAUAUUUCAAGUCUCUAAUAGGCAGAAUAUUUUACUCUUUAAAAUCCUGCCUUUCUGACCAAAAAAAAAAAAAAAAAUUCAUAUGGAUUCCAAUCCAUAGUAACAAGCACAGUUAAAACUCCUCAAUAAUCCCAUUUAUAUGAAGCAUGACACAUAAAUAAGCAGAUAAUAUUUAACCAAUGAAAAAGACUUCUACCUUCUUAUAAUUAAAAUUACACAUGUCUAAGAGGAAUUGUUUUAUCUUUUGAGUAGCUUUACCGAGUUGUAUUUAAAUUCUAAGGGCCAUUUGCUAAGCAGCAUUUAGCAUCUACUCAGGGCAGUUAUAUAGAUAAACUGCUGGACAGAAAAAUUGUAAAAUUUAGCAGCUUGAUUUUCUGUUAGCCUAUGAAAUGUUAUUGUCCUAUAAAAAUAACUUUAAACUGAUUUAAUAUUUCAUAUUUACAUUAUAUGAAAAUCAAUUACAUUAUAAAAGGAAUCCCUAAUGCAGAAACAAAGAUGCAACUUUCAAAAUUCUUAUUAUUCCUAUUUGUAUAUACACGAGAGAACCCAACCAGUGCCUGUGUUUGGGGGGAAAAGUCAACAGUGUAGUUCUAAACCUUAUCCCAAACAGAAAAUGUGGUUAAUGAUGUCACUUUCCUUGCUGGUCAUCAUUAGGCUUAAAUUAAAUGCUGAAGCUGUCAUCAAAGAGUUUACACUAAAAUCUUCAGGGCUUUAAAUAAAAGGUUAAGUCCAGCUUCCAAACACAAUUUUCCACAUUAGCAGCUCCAAUCUUCUUAAAUAAAGCUCUGUUUUCCUAUAUUUUUAUGACUGCUGAGACCCCACAGGGACCAAUAUUUGUAUUCAAAUUACAUUUCAUGGUUUCCCAUUGUUUCACAAUGAGUUCUAAUAAAUGGGAUUUACUAUAAUAAUCCAAGUAUGACAUAGCCGGUAUGCUUUCAUGAAUGUUUUUAUGUAGAUUUUCCUCCCAUGAACAUGAGUAAAUAAAUCUGUUUCCUGAAUGGAUUGUGGUUGCAUUUAAAGCUCUGUAAUAAUUCUAAUAAAUUUACUCUAUAGAGUUCUGUGUGUGGAAGGUAUAGAACAAUUGGAAGUCCAUGAAACCAUAACUAUAAUCAUAUAUUAUUCAGACAAAAUAUUGUAAUAAAAGUAGGUCCUUUCUUUCAUCAAAAACAUAUCUGAAAAUUUUCAGAUGCUUUAAUAUUAAAAGAUGACAAUGUUAUGUAUGCACAUUUUUAAGUUAGGUUGGAUAUGCAAACUGUACAAAACUAUAAAUCCAAAGAGUUUGUAAAGUUUAAACUCAAACACUGGUGGUAUAAAUAGAACUUGCACUUCUAAAUUAAGGAAGAUACCUAAAUGGUCUAGGAUGAGAUGAUAUAUUAUUUAAAGAGGGGACUAUCUCCCAAAUAACAACUUUAACACCUCAAAUAUGGGGGCUAGCUCAUUGAAAGAAGUCCAUACUUGAACUAUUAUUAUGUAUGUUCCGAUAAUUUUGUUGAAAAUACAAGUGGGAACAAAUUUCUAUUGAAGCAAACAUCUAAUUUUCAGUUAUGUCCAGAACUCUACUUUAUAAUGUUAAAUGUAGUAGUAUUUCUUAACUUUUAAAUACUUACUACUAUAGGAAUUGGUGCUGAUCAAAAUCUCUGGAGUGACUGUUAGCUGAUUAAAAUCUAUACCACUUACACAUCAUUUUUCCAUUCGUGUAAAAAACAAAAAAUCUUAACACAGUGAAUACUGCUGAGCAGAAUUUUUUCUUCUCAUUUUGCUCAAAGGACCAGAAUUUCCAUGCCCUUUAUACUCAUACUUGAAUGAGUCUUUUUAAUGUUCUCAUUUUGCUGUUUUUCCACCAAAUGUCUAUUUUCCUACUUCAUUCCCCAAGAUGUCUCACUGAGCAGGUCUGAAAAAGAAAGGUUAUUCUAAUACAAUUCCUAACAGAAAGUUGGUACAACACUGGCUAAUUCAGAAAUCGCUCCUCAGACUUAGAUUCCAAGAGUAUCAAAGAGAUUAGAUGGGAGGCUGGGCCAGGAACCCUUGUUUUAAUGUAUUUGUCCAUAAUUAACACUGGUGACCAUAUAAGGAACAAAGUAUAUCUGCACAUUUCACUGAGACAUCUACAUUGGAAAACCCAAACAAAAAGAAGCAAUUCAAAUAAAAAGACAACAUAAGAACGAAAAUAAGUUGGUCACAUUAACACUGGAAGCCAUCUUUAAGUGAGUGCUGUCAUAUUGUGUCACAGUAAUUUUUAGCCAAAUAUGGCGUUUGUAAAUUUAAACUUUCUCUCAUGGAAAGGGGGCUGGUACCUGUCAAAGUGUUAUUUUAUGCAACAAUAUAGUCACUUUUUAUUUUGGCAAUUAGAAGUAGACUCAAAGGAGAUUACAAUUUGGUUGCUGGCAGCCAUUCUGGGUUUCUUGAUUUUAGUACUCCAAAGAAUAUGGUGGUCUCAUGGAGUAGCUGACCACUAAGGAGGGGAGGAUUAAAAGGGAAUCACUUAUCAGUUUUUAGCAUAGGAUGCAUUAAGAAAUAUCAACGGAUAACUGACAUCGUUUUGUUAAGAAGUUAACUGUAUCGUAGCUCACUACUGCCAGAGCGGCAAUGGAUGUACAACGAAAGAGAUGAAAAAUACAAAAGUUAUUAAGCCACCUGAUUAAAAGAAAACCAAUAUUUAAAGGCAUUUAAUAGAUAUCAAGUAUAACUUUGAGGAGAAGAAUCAAUCUGUAUUACCAAAAAAAAAAUGUUUUGAUUUUCUGUAAGAUACAAUGAACUGGUACAUUAAAAGUCAAUUUUGUGUUACUGCAGUAUCUUUUAAUUCUUCUGAGUUGUAGAAUCUUAGCUAUUUUUCUUUGUGUCAAACUCUGUCAAUACAUUAUUUCCAAGAAAGGCAUUUAAUUCAUUCUUGUUCUGAUACAUUUGACUUCAAAUUGUAAAUACGUACAAUUUUCAUUUCCUAGUACUCUUGCAAAGUCAAAAAAAAAAAAAGAGCAUUUAUAUGGUGUCGCUAAAUCAACUAUAGUAUUAUCCCAAAAUAUAUUGACUUUUUUCUCUUUGUAUAUGACUCAAAGCAUAAUUAAUUUUGCCCACCAGUUCAGCAAUCCCAGAAAUCUAUUGUGUUGUUGAUUAGAUUAACACAUUUUAAAUGCUUUAUAACUUAAUCAUGAGUGCUGAAUUAAAAAAAGGUUUUUCUUUUCAUA